GUCUGCCGCCUCAGCCUCAGCCCCAACCUCAGCCGCCGCCGUUGCGCUUGCUCCCGGGCGGUCCUGGCCUGUGCCGCCGCCGCCCCCAGCGUCGGAGCCAUGGCGGGCGCCGCGUCCCCUUGCGCCAACGGCUGCGGGCCCGGCGCGCCCUCGGACGCCGAGGUGCUGCACCUCUGCCGCAGCCUCGAGGUGGGCACCGUCAUGACUUUGUUCUACUCCAAGAAGUCGCAGCGACCCGAGCGGAAGACCUUCCAGGUCAAGCUGGAGACGCGCCAGAUCACGUGGAGCCGGGGCGCCGACAAGAUCGAGGGGGCCAUUGACAUUCGUGAAAUUAAGGAGAUCCGCCCAGGGAAGACCUCACGGGACUUUGAUCGCUAUCAAGAGGACCCAGCUUUCCGGCCGGACCAGUCACAUUGCUUUGUCAUUCUCUAUGGAAUGGAAUUUCGCCUGAAAACGCUGAGCCUGCAAGCCACAUCUGAGGAUGAAGUGAACAUGUGGAUCAAGGGCUUAACUUGGCUGAUGGAGGAUACAUUGCAGGCACCCACACCCCUGCAGAUUGAGAGGUGGCUCCGGAAGCAGUUUUACUCAGUGGAUCGGAAUCGUGAGGAUCGUAUAUCAGCCAAGGACCUGAAGAACAUGCUGUCCCAGGUCAACUACCGGGUCCCCAACAUGCGCUUCCUCCGAGAGCGGCUGACGGACCUGGAGCAGCGCAGCGGGGACAUCACCUACGGGCAGUUUGCUCAGCUGUACCGCAGCCUCAUGUACAGCGCCCAGAAGACGAUGGACCUCCCCUUCUUGGAAGCCAGUACUCUGAGGGCUGGGGAGCGGCCGGAGCUUUGCCGAGUGUCCCUUCCUGAGUUCCAGCAGUUCCUUCUUGACUACCAGGGGGAGCUGUGGGCUGUUGAUCGCCUCCAGGUGCAGGAGUUCAUGCUCAGCUUCCUCCGAGACCCCUUACGAGAGAUCGAGGAGCCAUACUUCUUCCUGGAUGAGUUUGUCACCUUCCUGUUCUCCAAAGAGAACAGUGUGUGGAACUCGCAGCUGGAUGCAGUAUGCCCGGACACCAUGAACAACCCUCUUUCCCACUACUGGAUCUCCUCCUCGCACAACACGUACCUGACCGGGGACCAGUUCUCCAGUGAGUCCUCCUUGGAAGCCUAUGCUCGCUGCCUGCGGAUGGGCUGUCGCUGCAUUGAGUUGGACUGCUGGGACGGCCCGGAUGGGAUGCCAGUUAUUUACCAUGGGCACACCCUUACCACCAAGAUCAAGUUCUCAGAUGUCCUGCACACCAUCAAGGAGCAUGCCUUUGUGGCCUCAGAGUACCCAGUCAUCCUGUCCAUUGAGGACCACUGCAGCAUUGCCCAGCAGAGAAACAUGGCCCAAUACUUCAAGAAGGUGCUGGGGGACACACUCCUCACCAAGCCCGUGGAGAUCUCUGCCGACGGGCUCCCCUCACCCAACCAGCUUAAGAGGAAGAUCCUCAUCAAGCACAAGAAGCUGGCUGAGGGCAGUGCCUACGAGGAGGUGCCUACAUCCAUGAUGUACUCUGAGAACGACAUCAGCAACUCUAUCAAGAAUGGCAUCCUCUACCUGGAGGACCCUGUGAACCACGAAUGGUAUCCCCACUACUUUGUUCUGACCAGCAGCAAGAUCUACUACUCUGAGGAGACCAGCAGUGACCAGGGCAACGAGGAUGAGGAGGAGCCCAAGGAGGUCAGCAGCAGCACAGAGCUGCACUCCAAUGAGAAGUGGUUCCAUGGGAAGCUAGGGGCAGGGCGUGACGGGCGUCACAUCGCUGAGCGCCUGCUUACUGAGUACUGCAUCGAGACCGGAGCCCCUGACGGCUCCUUCCUCGUGCGAGAGAGUGAGACCUUCGUGGGCGACUACACGCUCUCUUUCUGGCGGAACGGGAAAGUCCAGCACUGCCGUAUCCACUCCCGGCAAGAUGCUGGGACCCCCAAGUUCUUCUUGACAGACAACCUCGUCUUUGACUCCCUCUAUGACCUCAUCACGCACUACCAGCAGGUGCCCCUGCGCUGUAAUGAGUUUGAGAUGCGACUUUCAGAGCCUGUCCCACAGACCAACGCCCACGAGAGCAAAGAGUGGUACCACGCGAGCCUGACCAGAGCACAGGCUGAGCACAUGCUAAUGCGCGUCCCUCGUGAUGGGGCCUUCCUGGUGCGGAAGCGGAAUGAACCCAACUCAUAUGCCAUCUCUUUCCGGGCUGAGGGCAAGAUCAAGCAUUGCCGUGUCCAGCAAGAGGGCCAGACAGUGAUGCUAGGGAACUCGGAGUUCGACAGCCUUGUUGACCUCAUCAGCUACUAUGAGAAACACCCGCUAUACCGCAAGAUGAAGCUGCGCUAUCCCAUCAACGAGGAGGCACUGGAGAAGAUUGGCACAGCUGAGCCUGACUACGGGGCCCUGUAUGAGGGACGCAACCCUGGCUUCUAUGUAGAGGCAAACCCUAUGCCAACUUUCAAGUGUGCAGUCAAAGCCCUCUUUGACUACAAGGCCCAGAGGGAGGACGAGCUGACCUUCAUCAAGAGCGCCAUCAUCCAGAAUGUGGAGAAGCAAGAGGGAGGCUGGUGGCGAGGGGACUACGGAGGGAAGAAGCAGCUGUGGUUCCCAUCAAACUACGUGGAAGAGAUGGUCAACCCCGUGGCCCUGGAGCCGGAGAGGGAGCACUUGGACGAGAACAGCCCCCUAGGGGACUUGCUGCGGGGGGUCUUGGAUGUGCCGGCUUGUCAGAUUGCCAUCCGUCCUGAGGGCAAGAACAACCGGCUCUUCGUCUUCUCCAUCAGCAUGGCGUCGGUGGCCCACUGGUCCCUGGAUGUUGCUGCCGACUCACAGGAGGAGCUGCAGGACUGGGUGAAAAAGAUCCGUGAAGUGGCCCAGACAGCAGACGCCAGGCUCACUGAAGGGAAGAUAAUGGAACGGAGGAAGAAGAUUGCCCUGGAGCUCUCUGAACUUGUCGUCUACUGCCGGCCUGUUCCCUUUGAUGAAGAGAAGAUUGGCACAGAACGUGCUUGCUACCGGGACAUGUCAUCCUUCCCGGAAACCAAGGCUGAGAAAUACGUGAACAAGGCCAAAGGCAAGAAGUUCCUUCAGUACAAUCGACUGCAGCUCUCCCGCAUCUACCCCAAGGGCCAGCGACUGGAUUCCUCCAACUACGAUCCUUUGCCCAUGUGGAUCUGUGGCAGUCAGCUUGUGGCCCUCAACUUCCAGACCCCUGACAAGCCUAUGCAGAUGAACCAGGCCCUCUUCAUGACGGGCAGGCACUGUGGCUACGUGCUGCAGCCAAGCACCAUGCGGGAUGAGGCCUUCGACCCCUUUGACAAGAGCAGCCUCCGCGGGCUGGAGCCAUGUGCCAUCUCUAUUGAGGUGCUGGGGGCCCGACAUCUGCCAAAGAAUGGCCGAGGCAUUGUGUGUCCUUUUGUGGAGAUUGAGGUGGCUGGAGCUGAGUAUGACAGCACCAAGCAGAAGACAGAGUUUGUGGGUCAGUCUGUCUUCCCAGUCAUCCUCCUCAUCCUGCUGGGGCACUGCAAGCCUCUCCCCACCAGUCAUCCCAUCCUCUCCCACGGUGACCUGAAGCCUUUUGUCGUUGCCUUCACAGUGGACAAUGGACUCAACCCUGUAUGGCCAGCCAAGCCCUUCCACUUCCAGAUCAGUAACCCUGAAUUUGCCUUUCUGCGCUUCGUGGUGUAUGAGGAAGACAUGUUUAGUGACCAGAAUUUCCUGGCUCAGGCUACUUUCCCAGUAAAAGGCCUGAAGACAGGAUACAGAGCAGUGCCUUUGAAGAACAACUACAGUGAGGACCUGGAGUUGGCCUCCCUGCUGAUCAAGAUUGACAUUUUCCCUGCCAAGCAGGAGAAUGGUGACCUCAGUCCCUUCAGUGGUACGUCCCUGCGGGAGCGGGGCUCAGAUGCCUCAGGCCAGCUGUUUCAUGGCCGAGCCCGGGAAGGCUCCUUUGAAUCCCGCUACCAGCAGCCGUUUGAGGACUUCCGCAUCUCCCAGGAGCAUCUCGCAGACCAUUUUGACAGUCGAGAACGAAGGGCCCCAAGAAGGACUCGGGUCAAUGGAGACAACCGCCUCUAGUUGUACCCCAGCCUCGUUGGAGAGCAGCAGGUGCUGUGCGCCUUGUAGAAUGCCGCGAACUGGGUUCUUUGGAAGCAGCCCCCUGUGGCGGCCUUCCGGGUCUCGCAGCCUGAAGCCUGGAUUCCAGCAGUGAAUGCUAGACAGAAACCAAGCCAUUAAUGAGAUGUUAUUACUGUUUUGGGCCUCCAUGCCCCAGCUCUGGAUGAAGGCAAAAACUGUACUGUGUUUCGCAUUAAGCACACACAUCUGGCCCUGACUUCUGGAGAUGGAUCCUUCCAUCUUGUGGGGCCAGGACCAUGGCCGAAGCCCCUUGGAGAGAGAGGCUGCCUCAGCCAGUGGCACAGGAGACUCCAAGGAGCUACUGACAUUCCUAAGAGUGGAGGAGGAGGAGGAGCCUUGCUGGGCCAGGGAAACAAAGUUUACAUUGUCCUGUAGCUUUAAAACCACAGCUGGGCAGGGUGAGAAGCUAGAUGCCCCUGCAGUUUGGCCCUGGAGCCAGGGCAGAGGAAUGUAGGGCCUGCAUGGAGAAGGGUUCUGCCCUGCCUGAGGAGGAGGACACAGCACAAGGGCACAUUGCCCAUGGCUGGGAACAUGACCCAGCCUGAAAGAUACAGGGGAUCAUGUUAAAAAUAGCAGUAUUAUUUUUCGUCUCAAUGGUAUUGUAACUAAGUUAUUUACUCCUCCUGCUCCUCACCCCUGUAGGGAAACCUUGGAGAGGAGAGUGGCAGGUGGGCUGCCUGCUGUGUUAAGAGGACUUAGUUUGUGAUGUAAGGCACUGUCAGGAAUGGGGGGCGGGCCAGGGUGGGAAGAGAAGAAAUAGCAGAGCCUAUUUUGGUGAGGUUUUUUGUUUUUAAGUCAAAGAAGACUCAGUAUGCUUUCCCUGAGGAAUGAAAAAGGGAUUGAGGAGUUGCCUGACUCCUGGGUGGGUGGGGUACAGGCAGUUAGGUGCUGAAUGAAGCUGCCAUCCUUGCUGCAGCUUCUAACUGGUAAAAAGAUCCAGGGAUGGAGAUGGGAAGGUUAGAAAGGCAGCCCUCACCUCUGAGGACAGAGGCCGGGGUCCAGGCCCGUGGGCGCAAAGGUGCCUCAUAGCAUAGCCAGCAUUCAGCACACACAAACCUACUGCCCACAUUUGGGCUCAGGGUUGGCCAUUUGCUAGUUCUGCUGCCCUCUUAAGAUCUGACUGCCAAAUAAAUCAUCCUCAUGUCCUUUUUCCUUUGACUUGUAUGCUCUUUCGGGGGCUCAGGAAAGCCUGUUGCAUGGGACAUGCUCACUAGAAACAGUCGCCAGAUGAUUAUUCUGCAGUAGAAGCAGGUAGGAAAUUUCUGGAAAUUUCUCAGGUUAAGCAGCAAGAGCUGUAACCCCUCCUCUGGGCUAACAGGAGUUGUGGGUCCACUCUCUCCUGCCCACCCUCUGAGGGUGUGUCUGAGCAGAGUACAUCCUGCCUGGGUUCUUUGUGGCCAGCCAGUUUUGGUGGUGAGCUGGAAACAACCAGAGCCCCUUUCCAGUUCCACAGAAACCUCUCCUUUCAAAAAUGUUGCAUUCAGUUCGUUAACACUGCCAGGUGCCAUUCUGAUUGCCUCUAGGACUUGGCAGCUGAAAUCUCUGGGCCCUUUCAACACAGUUGAAAGGCCCUUCUCUUCCUGAAGCUCUGUUUCCAUAGUUGGCUGUGCUGGGAUGGAACAAAAAUGACGCCACACAAAAAAUUUAAGAUAGAUCCGGUUCCGUGGAUGACAUGAACUGAUGAUAGCCAGUAUCAAACAGCGAUAGUGCUCAGGUUCUUGUGUGACUUUCUUUUACAGCUUCACAGUCCCAGUUCAUAGAGAGGAGGGUGGCUUUUUCCCAUACACAAGAAGGUGGUGGGUGGGAAUUCACCUGGGCCCUCAUGAUCCAUGUUUCCUCUCUAGGUUUUUAUGGCCUGGAGAGAAAGGUUUCCUAUCAGAGAAGGAAGAGGACUGUGUAGGCCCUUCUGUUAGGGCCCAUCCACGUUGGUUAGGACGUCCUUGGCGUGUUUGUUAGUGUUGACCCUUUUAGUUUUCAUCAAUACGUAUCUCUAUUUGCUGAACAAGUGUCUUUCUGGAACACAACCUGGGGAACAGACAGCUCUGCCUUUCUUAAGGCAGCUUUGUAGACCUGAGGCUCACCUCUCUUGGGCUCUGUAAGACAUUGCCUUUGCCUCACUGCAAAUGUUUUGAUUGUUCUUCCUAGUGGAAAACGUGCCAACUCUCAAGCAAAUUUAAAGAUCAUUUUCACUUCAAGAUUCCUCCAGACCUGACAAAUGUUGAUUGACCCAGAAGGCAGAGUGUUUGUUGGUGGGGAAGACCCUUACUUGGGGCCGAAUGCUUUGGCAUCAGGAGUUGUUUGCCCCAUCCCAUGCAUGCAGGCCGUGUCCCUACAGUGCGACAGCUCAGGGUUAUGACCUGUGGAGUCUCAACCCUAACAGCACAUUAGCACCACUUGGGGAGCUUCUGAAAAAUACUGGUACCCGGGGCCUUAGCAUAGGUAUUGUUCAAAACCUCUCAAGGUGAUUUAAAUGAGUAACAAGGGUUGAAAAACCCUGAUUUUGGCAGCACAAACCAAAAGAGCAGGCAGGGCCGGGAGAGGGAAGUCAGUGGUACCAGAAGGUAGAUGGGCUCCCUUGCAGGCUCCUUGUUCUCCUGCCAUCACCAGUAGAACCUUCUGGCUGACAGACCAGGGACAAGUAGACUGGGUUCAAAGUGACAGACCUUUCACUUUCAACAGCUUUGGCUCAGCAGACAUGUACACAUACAAAGUAGAGCCUACAAGGUCAGGGGCAUUCUGCCCCCGCCACAGGACUAAAGACUGCCCUGCGGGAAGAUGGCAGGAGCAGUUUCUGACCUCAGUUGAGUAUCUGUGGCCAUGAGCAGAAAAGGCAGGGGUCUGCCUCCUGACCAAGCACAUCUUGAACAUCACCUGAGAGCUUGAACAUCACUAAGGACCUAGACACUCACUUGUCUUUCAACUUGAGCCCAUCACUCACCAUGUGAGUUCUGUUGAGGGUGGGUAGAAAGCAAAUAGGUUCAGGUUAUCCCACCAGACUAACUCGGUGAAUGAAAGGAUCAUGCCUUCUUCACAUUUUAAUUAAAUGGAUCAAGCACA